AGAUGCAAAGCCGGUGGGGACCUGCCAAGAAGCCAGCCCACAAGGCCAUGGACUCCUCCACGCCAUCAGCUGGAGCAGUGGGCAGCCCCAGGAAGGGAGACGGGAGCGGCCAGGGGAAGGGCGAGGGGUCCCCCGGGCGACCCCCGAGGCUCAGGCGCCCGGACUCCAGUCCUGGGCCUCCGUUUUCCACCCUUGAACAAGCGGCUUCCACCUGUGAGCCAGCUGCCUCCUCUGAAAAUGGAAGCCCCUCAACUCAGAGGGUGUCGCUCUGGGACGUGGGUCAGGGGCCGGAGCAGGCAGGGAGAGGUGAGAGGAAAGGCUGGGGACCCUCACUUCUCCCUGCCCAAACCCUCGCUCGGGAGCAGACGGCUCCUCUGCCCGCAGGCACCCCUGCCUGGCAGCUCCCUCCAGCCCCCGUCGGGUCCGGGACGUCCUCUGAUGGGAAGGUUCCACCACAUCCGUGGCUGACAGAGCCAGCCCGUCCGAGGCCGGGGGGCGCUCGGGGUAAACAGGAAGCCCCAUCCCUCCCGCACUCUGCUUCACUCCCUCCUCCUGCACCUCCUGCAGCCCGGCUCCCGCGGCCGCGCCUGGUGCCCCUCUGUCUCGCGCCACCUGAGAUGCCCAGGCUGGCCUCUGCCAGGGGCUUAGUCUGCCCUCUCCUGGGGCUUCAGAGGCCAAAAGCACCCUGGUGAGGGGUCCGGGAGGCCCGGGAGGGCCCGGGGGGCUCUGCCAGGCCCCUCCACGCCUCUCUGCCCAGCCAGCACGCUCUGGGAAGCCUCCUGUUUGUCCGACGACACGUCCCCGUUAUCAGCGGAGAACACACACAGGAAGUCCGGCUGGGAAGGGCCCAUCCCAAUCCCGAUUACCCAGGACGGAGCAUAAAAAGCCGCCCUUCCUCGCCCGGGGGGAGCCUCCCUGCACCAAGCUGGCCCUGCACGGCUGCAAGGGAGGCUCCUGUGGACAGGCCAGGCAGGUGGGCCUCAGGAGGUGCCUCCAGGCGGCCAGUGGGCCUGAGGCCCCAGCAAGGGCUAGGGUCCAUCUCCAGUCCCAGGACACAGCAGCGGCCACCAUGGCCACGCCUGGGCUCCAGCAGCAUCAGAGCAGCCCCUGUGGUUGGCAGCAAAGUUCAGCUUGGCUGGGCCCGCUGUGAGGGGCUUCGCGCUACGCCCUGCGGUGUCCCGAGGGCUGAGGUCUCCUCAUCUUCUCCCUAGCAGUGGAUGAGCAACCCAACGGGGGCCCGGGGAGGGGAACUGGCCCCGAGGGAGAGGAACCCCAAAGCCACAUCUGUAGCCAGGAUGAGCAGUGUGAAUCCAGGCAGCCCCCAGGACCGGGGAGGCACAGGUGGCCCCCACCACCCGGAGGAGCAGCUCCUGCCCCUGUCCGGGGGAUGACUGAUUCUCCUCCGCCAGCCGUAGGGUGUGUGCUGUCCGGGCUCACGGGGACCCUGUCUCCGAGUCGUUCGUGCAGCGUGUGUACCAGCCCUUCCUCACCACCUGCGACGGGCACCGGGCCUGCAGCACCUACCGCAAUAUGCCAGCCGCCAUGCCGGAACGGAGGGAGCUGUGUCCAGCCUGGCCGCUGCCGCUGCCCUGCAGGAUGGCGGGGUGACACUUGCCAGUCAGAUGUGGAUGAAUGCAGUGCUAGGAGGGGCGGCUGUCCCCAGCGCUGCGUCAACACCGCCGGCAGUUACUGGUGCCAGUGUUGGGAGGGGCACAGCCUGUCUGCAGACGGUACACUCUGUGUGCCCAAGGGAGGGCCCCCCAGGGUGGCCCCCAACCCGACAGGAGUGGACAGUGCAAUGAAGGAAGAAGUGCAGAGGCUGCAGUCCAGGGUGGACCUGCUGGAGGAGAAGCUGCAGCUGGUGCUGGCCCCACUGCACAGCCUGGCCUCGCAGGCACUGGAGCAUGGGCUCCCGGACCCCGGCAGCCUCCUGGUGCACUCCUUCCAGCAGCUCGGCCGCAUCGACUCCCUGAGCGAGCAGAUUUCCUUCCUGGAGGAGCAGCUGGGGUCCUGCUCCUGCAAGAAAGACUCGUGACUGCCCAGCGCCCCAGGCUGGACUGAGCCCCUCACGCCGCCCUGCAGCCCCCAUGCCCCUGCCCAACAUGCUGGGGGUCCAGAAACCACCUCGGGGUGACUGAGCGGAAGGCCAGGCAGGGCCUUCCUCCUCUUCCUCCUCCCCUUCCUCGGGAGGCUCCCCAGACCCUGGCAUGGGAUGGGCUGGGAUCUUCUCUGUGAAUCCACCCCUGGCUACCCCCACCCUGGCUACCCCAACGGCAUCCCAAGGCCAGGUGGGCCCUCAGCUGAGGGAAGGUACGAGCUCCCUGCUGGAGCCUGGGACCCAUGGCACAGGCCAGGCAGCCCGGAGGCUGGGUGGGGCCUCAGUGGGGGCUGCUGCCUGACCCCCAGCACAAUAAAAAUGAAACGUGA